GAAUUCAAGAGCAAAUAUCCAUGGUUUUUAAAUCUCUUAAGUUUCAAGCGGAAGAUCAAACACAGUGUGUAAGCCUGGAGAACUAAAAAUAACCUAUAAUUCAAGUUGACAUUGUGAGAUGUAUGUAUACAACCAUCUUCUACAAUCUAUGUACUUUCUUAAUAGUAUGUCUGAUGACUAGAAAUGUUCUUAAUUUUAAUUAAGUCCAACUUAUAAAUUUGCUUUUAUGUUUAGUGCUUUUGUGUAUUUUUAAGGAGAUAUUUGCCUAUUCUGUCAUUCAGGAUCCAGUAAGAAGACAAAAAUCACACAGUAAUUUGAAUAGAGUUUAUAAAUACAAAUACUUAUUAAUUUCAUAAGGAAAUCAACUUUAAAGAAGGUAAAGACAACGCUGAGUAAUACCCUAGAGCUAAGAGAGAAUAUUGAAAGAAAAAACAAACUUGGAAAAUGGGGAAGGUACUCCCCAAGCCCGAGGUUGAAACUUCAUUUGAGAAUGCAUAGUCUUAGCAUCCUGGAUGCCAGAAAAGGUCAUUACAUUGCAUGUGUUUAGAAAGACACUUCUGUGGGGUAUAGGUGAACCAAGGCUGAGAGACUAAGAUUCCUUUUCAGGACUGAGUAGUAGGAAGCACCAGGUGAGCUGAGGCUUGUAGGCAGGGAACUAUAGUUGGCAUUGGCAAGCAAAUGAUAACCCCCCUUUGAAGUACAGGUGGGCAGCAAAUCACAGUUUGGACUGACAAGCUGGAAACACCCCUCCAGGGUCCAAAUAGGUUAUUUGGGAAGCCAGUCCCUAGAGUAACUGCAAGACUCAGUAAGAGUCUAGCCAUAUGGGUAUUGUUGAAAUUUGAUAGGAUGAGUAUUACUAAAUAUUUCUCAUUACACGCCUCUGGUAGAAGAGAGAGAAUAAUCAAAGAGAAGUACACACGAACUUCUCUUACAAGUGUCCCUGCGGCACCCUCUGCUGGCCAAGUUUAACAUCAUGAAUCUGUGAAGGAAAAAAUGUCCAUUGAGCCCAGUUCCAUUGUUGCAGAGUAAGCAAUGAAGUCUAUAUUUGAAACUGGGACAAUAAAUAAAUAACUGACACAUUUGCUGAUAUUAUCAAUGAUGUCCUUCUGUGUAAUUUUUGAAAGUUGUAAGGCUUUCCUUUUGAUAUUUCUAAAUACAACACAUGUAGAAUUUAUUUUUAUGAAUGAUGAGGUAAGGUCAAGGCAUAUUUUUUGAUAUGAAUACAUAGUUCAGUCAGAACUAUGUAAAAGAAAAUAAAAAUUGAAGGACCCCCCAAACUUGUGCAGAAGUAAAGACUAAGUCCUGAAGCUGAAUCAUUGCAACACUCUCUUCCACAUGAAUAACUGUUACUAACAUUAUAUAUCAGCCAGACUGGAAAGGUAAAUGGCCUCAGGCAUCUGGGAAGGGCUACCCACAGAUCAUUCAUAAGUAAAUUCUUUGCUUGCCUCCCAUAAACAAGGACACGCUAGUUGUAAAUUUAGGUCCACAAUCCAGGUCUAGCUCCUAAAACUCCACACCGAUUAUGUCACUUACAAGUUUAUCUUCCCAGGUGCAGAAAAGUCAAGAUUCAUUUUCUUCACCUACCCAGAGACGACUACAUGAUUGAGUCUUCCUUUACUCCCUUUCUCGCUUCAGACAUUCACCUUAUCUUACGUAAAAUGUAGAUUUACUGAACACUAACUGAAGUCUCAGGAAUGUAACUAUUUCCCCUACUGCCCAACCUACAUGCCUCCCCCUUCCCCCUUUUAAGGAAAUGGAUAAAUACACAAUGUCCUGAAAACCUUUGUGGAAAUAGCCACAGAUGUGUCGGUGGCUUUUGUUUUUCCCAGAAGUGCCCUAAACCUGGCUUAAUAAAC